GCCUGUCUGCGCAAGCGCUAACCAAGAAACGACGGUUUCGGGUAGAUUGUUGGUUAAGAAGAAAGCUGGGAAAGUGAAGGAGAGGGGGAAGAAAGGAAGUGAAAAGACUUUGGCUGUUGGAAUCUCAGAUCUGGAAUAGGCUGUAUAGGCUAUUUAUAAUCUCUAAUUGCCGAGGAACCUGAAGUUCAGAGUUAACCAGUGACUGACUCAGGACAUGCAAAAUGGCAAGACCCGAGGUAGAAGAGCUCACCUUUCCUGACUCUCAGUUUCCUGUUCCCUGAAAAUGUAAGCUAAGCUGGCAGCCCUGUCCCAGCAAGGGGGAGGUACAUGGAAGGCCACAGGAAGAAACAAGAUCUUGAGCUGAGCAAGAACAUCCCAGCAUCUUCAUUGACUUUAAAAGUAUAUUCUGGAGUCUUCCGUGGUUCACUAUUCCAGUACUACAGAGAUUCCUUAUAUUACAUGGCAGGAGGGGGGUAAACUGAGGGAUAGUGAAGACAACAAUAAAUUAAUCAAGAGCUUUCCUCAUAUCUCAGAACCUAUCCUCUGUAAGAAUGUCAGAAAAGGUUGACUGGUUACAAAGCCAAAAUGGAGUAUGCAAAGUUGAUGUCUAUUCUCCUGGAGACAACCAAGCCCAGGACUGGAAAAUGGACACCUCCACGGAUCCUGUCAGAGUGCUCAGCUGGCUCCGCAGAGACCUGGAGAAGAGUACAGCAGAGUUCCAAGAUGUUCGGUUCAAACCCGGAGAAUCAUUUGGUGGGGAAACGUCCAACUCAGGAGACCCACACAAAGGUUUCUCUGUAGACUAUUACAACACCACCACCAAGGGCACUCCAGAAAGAUUGCAUUUUGAGAUGACUCACAAAGAGAUUCCUUGCCAGGGCCCCAGGGCCCAACUUGGCAACGGGAGUUCAGUAGAUGAAGUUUCCUUCUAUGCUAACCGCCUCACGAAUCUAGUCAUAGCCAUGGCCCGCAAAGAGAUCAAUGAGAAGAUCGAUGGCUCUGAAAACAAAUGUGUCUAUCAGUCAUUGUACAUGGGGAAUGAACCCACACCCACCAAAAGCCUCAGUAAGAUAGCAUCAGAGCUUGUGAAUGAGACCGUCUCUGCAUGUUCCAGGAAUGCUGCCCCAGACAAGGCUCCUGGCUCUGGAGACAGAGUCUCGGGAUCAUCACAAAGUCCCCCAAAUUUGAAAUACAAGUCCACUUUGAAGAUCAAGGAGAGCACCAAAGAAAGACAGGGUCCAGAUGACAAGCCUCCUUCUAAGAAGUCUUUCUUCUAUAAGGAAGUGUUUGAAUCUCGUAAUGGAGAUUAUGCCAGAGAGGGUGGAAGGUUCUUUCCUCGGGAGAGAAAGAGGUUUCGAGGGCAGGAAAGGCCUGAUGACUUUACGGCUUCUGUUAGUGAAGGGAUCAUGACCUAUGCUAACAGUGUGGUAUCUGAUAUGAUGGUCUCCAUCAUGAAGACACUGAAGAUCCAAGUGAAAGACACAACCAUUGCCACCAUCCUACUGAAGAAGGUUCUGCUCAAGCAUGCAAAAGAGGUGGUCUCGGAUCUCAUCGACUCCUUCUUGAGGAAUCUCCACAGCGUCACAGGGACCCUCAUGACUGACACACAGUUUGUCUCGGCUGUGAAAAGAACUGUCUUCUCUCAUGGAAGCCAAAAGGCCACAGAUAUCAUGGAUGCCAUGCUAAGGAAGCUGUACAAUGUAAUGUUUGCCAAGAAAGUCCCUGAGCAUGUCAGGAAAGCCCAAGACAAGGCUGAGAGUUAUUCCCUCAUCUCCAUGAAAGGAAUGGGUGAUCCUAAAAACCGAAAUGUGAACUUUGCCAUGAAAUCUGAAACUAAAUUGAGAGAAAAAAUGUAUUCUGAACCCAAAUCAGAGGAGGAGACUUGUGCGAAAACUCUGGGUGAGCACAUUAUCAAAGAGGGGCUUACCUUGUGGCAUAAAACUCAGCAGAAAGAAUGUAAAUCUCUAGGUUUCCAGCAUGCAGCAUUUGAAGCUCCCAACACACAGCGUAAGCCUGCAUCAGACAUUUCCUUUGAGUACCCUGAAGAUAUUGGCAACCUCAGCCUUCCUCCAUAUCCUCCAGAGAAACCUGAGAAUUUUAUGUAUGAUUCAGACUCCUGGGCCGAGGACCUGAUCGUGUCUGCCCUGCUUCUGAUUCAAUAUCACCUGGCCCAGGGAGGAAGAAGGGAUGCACGGAGCUUCGUUGAAGCUGCUGGCACCACCAACUUUCCUGCCAAUGAACCUCCUGUAGCUCCCGAUGAAUCUUGCCUUAAGUCUGCUCCCAUUGUAGGUGACCAAGAACAAGCAGAAAAGAAGGACCUAAGGAGUGUUUUCUUUAAUUUCAUCCGGAACUUACUUAGUGAGACCAUUUUCAAGCGUGACCAGAGCCCUGAACCCAAGGUGCCGGAACAGCCAGUUAAGGAAGAUAGGAAGUUGUGUGAAAGACCGUUGGCGUCUUCUCCCCCCAGGCUAUAUGAGGAUGAUGAGACCCCUGGUGCCCUUUCUGGGCUGACCAAGAUGGCUGUCAGCCAGAUAGAUGGCCACAUGAGUGGGCAGAUGGUAGAACAUCUGAUGAACUCAGUGAUGAAGCUGUGUGUCAUCAUUGCUAAGUCCUGUGAUGCUUCGUUGGCAGAGCUGGGAGAUGACAAGUCUGGAGAUGCCAGUAGGCUAACUUCGGCCUUCCCAGAUAGUUUAUAUGAGUGCUUACCAGCCAAGGGCACAGGGUCAGCAGAAGCUGUCCUGCAGAAUGCCUAUCAAGCUAUCCAUAAUGAAAUGAGAGGCACAUCAGGACAGCCCCCUGAAGGGUGUGCAGCACCCACGGUGAUUGUCAGCAAUCACAACCUAACGGACACAGUUCAGAACAAGCAACUCCAAGCCGUCCUUCAAUGGGUAGCUGCCUCUGAGCUCAAUGUCCCUAUUUUGUAUUUUGCUGGUGAUGAUGAAGGGAUCCAGGAGAAGCUACUUCAGCUCUCAGCUGCUGCUGUGGACAAAGGAUGCAGUGUGGGCGAGGUUCUGCAGUCGGUGCUGCGCUAUGAGAAGGAGCGCCAGCUGAAUGAGGCGGUGGGGAAUGUCACACCGCUGCAGCUGCUGGACUGGCUGAUGGUGAACCUGUAAUCGGCAACCCCACUGCUUUCCCCUCUUCUGGCAGUGGGGCCGGCCCUUAUCCCCGCCCUUCUUUCUCACUUCCACAUCUCCCCCUCUAUAUCCUCACAGAGCCCUAACAUUAUCUUCACACCACUCUCAUCAAAGACAUGUCAUCUUGUGCUAGCCACUGGAUUUUGCAGAUUUUCCUGUCCAUGCAAGCAAGGACGUAAAAUUAAAAAAUUACAAUUAAA